GUAGUGCCCCGGCCGCGGCGGCGAGGGGCGCUCCCUCUUCAGCUAAGCCGUUAGCGCCGAGCCCGCCCGGGAGCGGGUCGCCGGCCGCGGCGGGCGCCCCUGCCAGUGAGCCCCUGUCCGAAGUGAGCCACGGCAUUGACUCGGGGCUGCCCGGGGGCAGGGCACUGAGGAGGGAGUUGCGCGCGCGAGGCGAGGGCGAUGGGGCCAAGAAGAACCGGGGCGAUAGCGCGGCAGCGGUGACAGCUGGGACCCGCCGCGGUCGGGCUGCCCCCUCCCCUCGCCCCGACCGCUCCCCUGCUGGUGAGGGCCUGCGGAGGCGGCGGCGGCGGCGCCCUUGGUGGCAGUGGUGGCGGCGGAGCAGCCUCCCGGGAUCGUGUCCGGAGCUCGAGGAGAGGGUGGUGCCCGGCGAGCUAUGCACGGGGGCGGCGGCGUCUCCUCCUGUUCCGCCUCCUCAGUCUCCUCGGUCUCGCAGAAUCCGCCGGCGGCGGCGGCGCCAGGACAUGGAGCUCGAGAACAUCGUGGCCAACUCGCUGCUGCUGAAAGCGCGUCAAGGAGGAUAUGGCAAAAAAAGUGGUCGUAGUAAAAAAUGGAAGGAGAUACUGACACUGCCUCCUGUCAGCCAGUGCAGUGAGCUUAGACAUUCCAUUGAAAAGGAUUAUAGCAGUCUUUGUGACAAGCAACCGAUAGGAAGACGUCUCUUCAGGCAGUUCUGUGAUACCAAACCCACUCUAAAGAGGCACAUUGAAUUCUUGGAUGCAGUGGCAGAAUAUGAAGUUGCCGAUGAUGAGGACCGAAGUGAUUGUGGACUGUCAAUCUUAGAUAGAUUCUUCAAUGAUAAGUUGGCAGCCCCUUUACCAGAAAUACCUCCAGAUGUUGUGACAGAAUGUAGAUUGGGACUGAAGGAGGAGAACCCUUCCAAAAAAGCCUUUGAGGAAUGUACUAGAGUUGCCCAUAACUACCUAAGAGGGGAACCAUUUGAAGAAUACCAAGAAAGCUCAUAUUUUUCUCAGUUUUUACAAUGGAAAUGGCUGGAAAGGCAACCCGUAACAAAGAACACAUUUAGACAUUACAGAGUUCUAGGAAAAGGCGGAUUUGGAGAGCAGUCCCCUGUGGGGUGUGCAGUGGAUGGGAGUUGGAAGAAACAGCAGCCUAAUGUUGAUGACACAGAGGCACGGGGACCAGAACCUGAGGCUCAUGAUACUAUUUUUUCCACUUUUGUUUGCGCCUGUCAAGUGCGAGCCACAGGAAAAAUGUAUGCCUGCAAAAAGCUACAAAAAAAAAGAAUAAAGAAGAGGAAAGGUGAAGCUAUGGCUCUAAAUGAGAAAAGAAUUCUGGAGAAAGUGCAAAGUAGAUUCGUAGUUAGUUUAGCCUACGCUUAUGAAACCAAAGAUGCCUUGUGCUUGGUGCUCACCAUUAUGAAUGGAGGGGAUUUGAAGUUUCACAUUUACAACCUGGGCAAUCCCGGCUUUGAUGAGCAGAGAGCCGUUUUCUAUGCUGCAGAGCUGUGUUGCGGCUUGGAAGAUUUACAGAGGGAAAGAAUUGUAUACAGAGACUUGAAGCCUGAGAAUAUUCUCCUUGAUGAUCGUGGACACAUCCGGAUUUCAGACCUCGGUUUGGCCACAGAGAUCCCAGAAGGACAGAGGGUUCGAGGAAGAGUUGGAACAGUCGGCUACAUGGCACCUGAAGUUGUCAAUAAUGAAAAGUAUACGUUUAGUCCCGAUUGGUGGGGACUUGGCUGUCUGAUCUAUGAAAUGAUUCAGGGACAUUCUCCAUUCAAAAAAUACAAAGAGAAAGUCAAAUGGGAGGAGGUCGAUCAAAGAAUCAAGAAUGAUACCGAGGAGUAUUCUGAGAAGUUUUCAGAGGAUGCCAAAUCUAUCUGCAGGAUGUUACUCACCAAGAAUCCAAGCAAGCGGCUGGGCUGCAGGGGCGAGGGAGCGGCUGGGGUGAAGCAGCACCCCGUGUUCAAGGACAUCAACUUCAGGAGGCUGGAGGCAAACAUGCUGGAGCCCCCUUUCUGUCCUGAUCCUCAUGCCGUUUACUGUAAGGACGUCCUGGAUAUCGAGCAGUUCUCGGUGGUGAAAGGGAUCUACCUGGACACCGCAGAUGAAGACUUCUAUGCUCGGUUUGCUACCGGGUGUGUCUCCAUCCCCUGGCAGAAUGAGAUGAUCGAAUCUGGGUGUUUCAAAGACAUCAACAAAAGUGAAAGUGAGGAAGCUUUGCCAUUAGAUCUAGACAAGAACAUACAUACCCCGGUUUCCAGACCAAACAGAGGCUUCUUCUAUAGACUCUUCAGAAGAGGGGCAGUUUUAUACAGUCUGAGAGCCACAUGGUGCUAGGUGGAGGCCAGCCAGAACAAUGAGAACACCCUCGCAGUGAGGUUUGUUGCUGGGAUGAAGACUGUUCUGAUCCAAAACAGGACUACCUUCCAGCAUUUACAAACAGGUUCCCGUGUCGCUGACAAAAUAGUUUACACUGGGCUCAGAAAUCGGCAUCCUGUGGAACCUUCGUCAGAUGGCACUCACAGUGCAUCUCUCCCUGCUCUGGCUCUUAGACUCACCUCCUUCGCCCGCUGCACGGGGAAAGUGGAUUCCUUUUUGAAAAGGGAAUCCUGGCUGGGUGCGGUGGCUCACGCCUGUAAUCCCAGCACUUUGGGAGGCCGAGG